ACAGAUAGCAAGUCCUAGUCAGAGCUGCCGCUACAUUUAGGAGAAACAGCGGUGUCUGCGGCUCCCACCCUUCGGGGGGCCCGUGGGGGGGGCGGUGUCAGGGGCAUGGACGCCACCCCCCAGGGGUCUCUGCUGCCGGCUACUCUCCUCUCCACGUGCUGUGAGUUGAGUUGCGGGGGACUUGGGGUUUGGGCCCCUAUUUCCAAGGCAAGUGGGGGUUUGGGAGGAGCUGGUUCUUGGGGGAGUUUUCACCAGGUCUCUCCUUCCAAAAAAUGAGCCCCCUUACUCCCCAGCUCUCUAGAGGGAGGAAGAGGGGCCCAGGAAAAGUGGUAUUGCAAUCUUCUGCAAAGGGGUCAUAGCAUGCACAAGAAAUGAGGAGUAGGUUGGAGGAACUGAAAUUCUUGGAGGGAAGAUGGAGAAAUCAAGUCCUUGAUCUUGAGAUAGAGGUAACAAUUUCACACUUUUCCUUCCCCUGAGAAAAGUGCAGUCCCCCACUCAGGAAGACAGGAUGUGGGACACAUUCAAAAUAAGGUUUACCUAGAUCCCUGGGGCAAUGGAGAGUGAGAGAGUUCUGGGGGUGAUCCGACAUCGGGGUUCCUUCCCCAUCCCUGGGCAGAGAGAUCUGUCUAGGCAAGCCGACUGGGGGUCAGAUUACCUAAGACCCUGAGAGAACAUCUGGAAGCCCACCUGGGACUAAAGCUAGGAUAAUGGGAGCAGGGUCGUUUUCUGCAUGACCUGGGGUCUCUGAGCCAGUCAAUGCUUACUCUUCCUGAGGACAUCUGAGCUUCAGGGAAGGAAAAGGAAGCCCAUUGUUGGGGGCAGGGGAAACCCUAAUCUUCCAUUGCCAUGGGGCUCUUGGACCCUGUGUCCCCUGACUCCAUGGACAAUAAAUGCAGGGGGUGCCCCUAAGCUCAAAGCCAUUUCAUUUUGAUUUCUCUUCCUACCUUCUCUACCCCAAGACACACAAACACACACACACACACCCUCUCCAGAGUGCUGACUGCAGAGGACCUCACCCCAGAACAUAAGAUGCUGGAGUGCUAGGUUUAGAGUCACAUACCCAGGCAGUUUCUCCCCAGGACCUGGUCAACCAUCCAGGCCAUCUGUGGUUCCUAUGGCACACUCCUCCAUCCCCCACCCACUAGCCAGCCCACGUUUCCGUGGAGUGGGAGGAGAGGAUCAUUCCCAGGAAAGAGAAGGGAAGGUGGAAGAGUCCCAAAUCCUAUUCUAAACCUUUCCCUGUAUGGUCCAUAUCUCCUAGAGGACCCUGGGUGCUUUGGGGAAGGGCUCUGGACCUCUCUCAGAGCAGAUUGCAGCUCAGAGAGCUCCUCAGAGGCAAGCAUGUGAAGAAAAAUCAGGCUUCUGUGUUGGGAUCUUCCAGUUCCCCUCCCCAUUUGCAGGCUGUCUCCACUAGGAGAAAAAACCCAAGGGAAAUGAGGCUGGCCCAAGAGCAGCAGUGAUCGUGGGUAGGUCUCAGGGAGGAUUUCUAGUGGGAAUUUCCUAAUGUUCCACCCUUGUGCACUGGAGGGUUUCCACUGACUUUCCACAGCUUUCAUUUCUUUCUCGUUUGUAAGCAUGUUGAGGGGAGGGAAUGGAGCGGAGUGAGUGAGGUCCAAGGAGGGAAGAAUGAGAAAGACUGUGUAUCAGUCUUGGGGUGAACUUCAAAACAGCCUGCGAGGAGAGCCAUUGGUGGCUGCACUGGCUACAGCUGGGGAAGGGAUGGUGGAAGUCCUUAGGGCAGGGAGGGCUCCAUUACCCGCCUGCCCCCCUCCCCAAAAAGCCCCCAGUCUAUUGAUUUCAGGAAAUCACUAGGGGGAUCUGGGCCUGGGUCUUUGGCCCCGGGGCUGCCCCUGAGGUGCUGCACACCCCAGCUGGAGGUGAUGGCACCAAAAUAUCUGGUACCUCCUUCCCCUGAAAAUCAUCGUGGAACUUGCACAGUUCUAUCCAGUUCAGGUACAUCAUUCCAUUUGACCCUCACAACUUUCUGAGCCUGGGGGGCAGUUAGGGCUGAAUGUGUUAUUCCCAGAAAUAGAGGCCAGGCAACACGAAGGGACUCGCCCAGGGCCCCCCAGGGCUCGGUGCUGGCCCUGAUGCCCCGUGCCUCCCCAUCUCCCGAGGGGCCACUCAUUCGGCAAACCUUUAUUAAGCCCCUCCAGGACCCCCGACGCCGCCUAGGCGCCCAGCGACGCGCGGCAGGUGGCAGCAGCUCGGGCCCCCGCCGCACUCCAGGCGCCCGCAGCGCUCGCCCUGACGCGGCCGCCAUGGCGCAGGAGAACGCGGCCUUCUCGCCCGGGCAGGAGGAGCCGCCGCGGCGCCGCGGCCGCCAGCGCUACGUGGAGAAGGAUGGCCGGUGCAACGUGCAGCAGGGCAACGUGCGCGAGACAUACCGCUACCUGACGGACCUGUUCACCACGCUGGUGGACCUGCAGUGGCGCCUCAGCCUGUUGUUCUUCGUCCUGGCCUACGCGCUCACCUGGCUCUUCUUCGGCGCCAUCUGGUGGCUGAUCGCCUACGGCCGCGGCGACCUGGAGCACCUGGAGGACACCGCGUGGACGCCGUGCGUCAACAACCUCAACGGCUUCGUGGCCGCCUUCCUCUUCUCCAUCGAGACCGAGACCACCAUCGGCUACGGGCACCGCGUCAUCACCGACCAGUGCCCCGAGGGCAUCGUGCUGCUGCUGCUGCAGGCCAUCCUGGGCUCCAUGGUGAACGCCUUCAUGGUGGGCUGCAUGUUCGUCAAGAUCUCGCAGCCCAACAAGCGCGCAGCCACGCUCGUCUUCUCCUCGCACGCCGUGGUGUCGCUGCGCGACGGGCGCCUCUGCCUCAUGUUCCGCGUGGGCGACUUGCGCUCCUCACACAUAGUGGAGGCCUCCAUCCGCGCCAAGCUCAUCCGCUCGCGCCAGACGCUGGAGGGCGAGUUCAUCCCGCUGCACCAGACCGACCUCAGCGUGGGCUUCGACACGGGAGACGACCGCCUCUUCCUCGUCUCGCCGCUGGUUAUCAGCCACGAGAUCGACGCCGCCAGCCCCUUCUGGGAGGCGUCGCGCCGUGCCCUCGAGAGGGACGACUUCGAGAUCGUCGUUAUCCUCGAGGGCAUGGUGGAAGCCACGGGAAUGACAUGCCAAGCUCGGAGCUCCUACCUGGUAGACGAGGUGCUGUGGGGCCACCGCUUCACGUCAGUGCUGACUCUGGAGGACGGCUUCUACGAAGUGGACUAUGCCAGCUUUCACGAGACUUUUGAGGUGCCCACACCUUCGUGCAGUGCUCGAGAGCUGGCAGAGGCUGCCGCCCGCCUUGAUGCCCAUCUCUACUGGUCCAUCCCCAGCCGGCUGGAUGAGAAGGUGGAGGAGGAGGGGGCGGGGGAGGGGGCGGGUGGGGAAGCUGGGGCUGACAAGGAGCAGAAUGGCUGCCUGCCACCCCCAGAGAGUGAGUCCAAGGUGUGACCAGCUUCCUCCAGACCCCUGUGGCAGACCGGGGGCCAGACACAGAUACAUGGGGAACUGCAUAUCGGAGGUGGUGGAGGAGGAGGAGGAGGAGGAAGGCAAAGCCCCUGGAAAUGUGCUAAAGUUGGAAAGUCCCCGUCCCCCAGAACCUCAAGUCUAGAAACCAGUAUGGAAGGGAGGGGUCCUGAUUUCAGGGAAAUGGAGGGUGGGGCCGGGUGAAAAUGCCAGUCUGUGUUUGACCUUCACAUUUGUUCAUGAGUGGAUGGAUGGACAGAAUGAUGGACUUUUGGGGGUUGGAUGGGAAGAUGGUAGCAGAUAAAGACAGCUGACAGAUACAUAGAUGGACCAGUAGACAACUGGUCCACUCAGGGCUGCCACUAACCUGUAGAACACCCCUGUGCAAAUUUUAAAAAGGAACCCUUUUCCUCCAGACAGAUACAGCCCCAAACCAGGGUGCAUGGCUUGGGGAGCAGAGUAUAGGAUGGAUUGCAGUCCCCAGUCACCUCUUCUGCCAGCCUCCCCACAUAUGGCACAACUGUCUAAUGACACGGUAGGCCAAGCUGAAGUGAAGGAGAAAGGAGCCGGACCAAGAUGGGCACAUGAGGAGGGUGCCCUCCUAGCUCCACCCUCACCAGGAUGAAGGCGUGCAAGGGGCUCAGCAAGGUGUGAAUGACCUUAGUCCGCAAGUUCAGGGAAGCAGGCAGAGCGGGGAGGUGCCUGAGCUGGGGCCUGGAGAGGGGCCUGGGAAAGGAAAACCAGGGAUAGCUAUUUUCUUACAGUGGAGUGAGAUCUUACAGGUAUCAGGCACAGGCAGGAAGAGAGAGAGAGAGGUUCUGGGGAGGAAGGGCCAGGAGAGAGAUCUAGAAAGUGGGUUCACUAGAGCUGGGAAACAGGGAGCCCCUAGGAAAGCAGUGUGUCCUUGGGGCACAGUCAUUCACAUCACUGAUUGGGUGCCAUGUGGAGUGGACAUUCAAAAACCUGGUUCCUGUCCUCAAAAUAAGGGGCACCUGGGAAAACAGAGGAAUCUACCUGUGGUGACUGAACGAGGGAUAAUUCAAACUGACAACCUGUGCAGUCCCGUGGAGGGUAGGGGAGUGUGGGUGAUCAGAAGGCUGGGGCCAGUGUAAGGCAUAGGGAAUAUGUAAGUCAGGAGUUAGAAAUCUCCAGUGUGCGUUGGAAUCACCUGGAGGGCUUGGUAAAACACAGAUUUUUGGGCUCCACUCCAAGGGUUUCUGACCCAAGAGGUGGGGACCAAAACCAUGCAUUCCUAAGAAGUCCCCAGGUCAUGCUGCUGUUGCUGGACUGAGGACCACACUUUGAGAACCUGUGCUCUAAGUGAAUACUUGGAAGUCGUUUCAGGACAUGGGGCAUAGAAACUGAGGAGUAGCUGAGAGGAAGAUGAAGAGAAGCUGAGAAGAAGCUGAGGAUCCUCACAGGAGCAGACAGAGAAAUGUGAAGGGUGGGGUUUUAUGUGUGGGAAAGGGACCCGAAGCCCAGGCUGAAGAGUUUAACUUUGGGCCCAGAAACUCAACCAUCAAUGGAAACAGGGCAGUGACAAGUGGAGGGGGUGUCUGGAAGCUGAGCAGGCCCGACAGAGAGAUGAAGCCAUCAGAAGGACUUGAGGGGGCUCCUGGGGAGGUCGGGGGGAGGUGGAGCAGGAAGAGUUUUAGGGGCAAAGGACAGAACCCCUUGUAGGACUGGAGGCAAGAUUGAAUGUGGGAGAAAAUCGGAGAGAAGCGAUAGGAGUUAGAACAUCUGGAUGUGUCUGCAGCCUGCUGUCAGCCCAAUUGGGCCAGGGGGUCCCAAAGACGCAUAUUCUCACCCCACCUCCACCUGCUUCCUGAUCACAUCCCAGUCACCAGCGGCAGCUUCCUGGAUAGUGAGGGAGAACAACUGCAAGUUGAGAGAGGCAGAGGGGUGGAAGGGACCUGAAGCUGGCCUGGAGAAAAGCAUAGGCCCAGGAGAGCCUGCCCUGGGACAGCGCCUGUCUCCCACACAGCAGCACUGGCCCAGCAAGGACCUCCUCCCUUGGCCCUGGCCACAUCCCACUCCUGCCCUUUCAUAAGCCCCCUGGGGAAAGCACUCCAGUCUUCUCUGUUCCAGGCUGGGCAGAUAGGGUCCUAUGGGGCACAGCCAGGGUCCUAUGGGCAUAGCCAGGGCCCUAUGGGUCCUCUGGAAGCAAGAAAGGGGGCCAUGGAAGCAGCCCAGACAGCUGGGGUUCACUCAGAGAGGACCCAAGUCCCAGUCCCUUCCUUUCAGUCAAAACACGGAUAUCUUUGCCUCAGGUCACAGGGCCACUGGGGCCCUGUCAUCAAAGAUGAGAUUCCUGAAGCCUGGCAUUGACUGGUCCCCUAAGAACAGAUGUUGGGAUGGAGAAUGGGGAUUCAUUUGGGUUUCAGUAAAACAGGGGGGUCUGGACAAGAGCGGGUGGGCUACUUGGUAUCCACACACACGCACUCACACAGGAGCCAACCCAUUGCAGCUGAACAAGCAGAGAAACUCAGUCUGGAAAGGCCCCUCCUGCCUGCUGAAGUCACUGAGACCCUGCCACACCUCUCCUCGCCACUGUCACCACUCAGGGCACCACUGUACAGUGCAACAAGUCAGGAGACCUAGGUCCUACUCCUGACACUUGCUAAUUAGCUCUAUGACUCUGGGCAAAUCGCAUAUCUGGGCCUCAGUUUCCUCAUCUGUAAAAAUGACAGCAAACUCGUAAUGCUCAAUAAAUGUUUAAAUAACAACUGAA